CCACUGUGAAUAUAGUUCAGCUCUUAGGUGUGCUUAUGAUGACCUUAUUUUCUGGACCAAAAUUCAGGACAUAUUUUGUGUCUGUAAAGUAAAGAAGGAUUAUUCUUCUGCCUCUCUGCUGGCUUGUGCUAAGGUCUUUGCAGAUGUUUUUCUCUUGACCACCCCUUAACUCUUGGUGUUUGUCUUUGUUGUUGGCCUUCUUUUCUUAUUCUCUGGUAACUACUCCUUAUAUGCUGAUGUCUCCCAAAUCUUAAUUUUCAGCCCAGGUCUUACCCCUGAACUUCAUGUAGACAGUUUUCUCUGCAACAGCCCUAACUGGAUUUUCCCUGCACUCAGGGUGUUCAAGAUGAACUCAACAUUGCCUUCCACAAAAAUCACUUACUGAUGAAUGACACCACCAUUCAUAUGACACCCUACAUCCAGCCAGCCCCCAAGUCCUGAUGCUUCUACUUCCUGACUGCUCUAAAAUCUGUCCUCUCUCUUCUAGGCCUUCAUCCUUUUUUACUUGGUUUGCUGCCUACAUCCUCCAAACUGGUUACUUCAGGGUAACCCCGCCUUUUCCAGGCUGCCCCCAAACAAACAAGAACAAGCGUGGUUUUGUGACCAGCUCCUCAUCCUCAGCAUCGGUGGCCUUCUGCCUGUUCUUUGUCCAGGCUGGAUUCUCACGACUCCUGCUCGCCUUGCCUCCCUGGGCGGCAGAGGCAAUGCUCCUGCAGAAUGUGCUCCUACGCCCUCUCCACUUUCCUCUGCCAAAUGCCUUUUCACCCUGCAUUUCAGACACCAUUAUUUCUGAGAAGCUUUGUUUAACCCUGCCUGAGCCCGGGCUCUGUAGUCAGAGUUAGAUGCCCCCACGUGCCCCUAUCACAGCAUGGGCAUCUCCAUACCUUAGCUCUUACCUUGCUUUGUUGUAAUGUUCUAUGACCUGUCUCCCCCUGUGAGCUUCCUGACAACAGAGGUGGCACUUGUUUUUCUUUGUGGUUCCAGUGUGUUUCACAUACCAGUACCUAGUAGGUGUUUGAUAAAUGUGUGUCGUGUAAAUUAAUGAAUCAACAAGUCAAUGAAUGAAUGUAUAUAAGUGCACUUGUGAGGCAGUGGGGGAGAAUUCCUAACUUCUAGAGUUUAGUAGUCUUGGAAAAUCCAAGUUGUCAGAACCUGUUGUUCACUAUCUGCAUCACUAUAAGCAGACUCCUAAAGAUUGCUAGAAUAUAGCACAAAGGAUAUGUCUUUGCAGGCUAGGAUGGGUAGGGGCAUGAACCUGGUGUGGUGCUUUGCCAUAUCCAGUUGGCCCUUCUUAUCUGUGGGUUCUGCAUCCAUGGAUUCAACAAAACUUGGAUGGAAAGUAUUUGGGGGAAGUGGGGAGGAAGGAUGGUUGUAUCUGCACUGAAUGCGUAUAGACUUUUUUUCCUUUAUUAUUUCCUGAACAAUACAGUAUAACAGCUGUUUACAUACCAUUUACAUAGUGUUAGGUAUUAUAAGUAAUUUAGAGAUUAAAGCCUACGAGAGGAUGUAUGUAGGUCAUAUGCAAAUACUGUACCAUUUUAUAUUAGAGACUUGAGCAUACAAAAUCUGGGGGAGAUCCUGGAACCAGUCCCCAUGGAUACAGUCAUGUGUCACCUAACAGUGGGGAUACAUUCUGAGACAUAUGUCAUUAGGCAGUUUAGUCAUUGUGUGAUUGCCAUAGAAUGUACUCACACAAAACUAUAUGGUCUACCCACUACGUCCCUAGGCUGUAUGAUAUAUAUAGCCUGUCAUUCCUAGGCGACAAAUUUGUGUAUCAUGUAACUAUACUGAAUAAUGUAGGCAACUGUAACACAAAUGGACAGUUCGUGUUUGGUUAAAGAGAGACAGUGGACAGUAUUGGCCAAGCGUAUACCAUGCAAUGCCUUCUCCAUGUUCAUGCAUGUCUUUUAACCCGGAAACAAGAAGACUGUCCAUAGGUCUAGACAAUGGUACAAUCUCAGAGUUUAUAUUGUCAGAAGAUUAUAACAAGAUGACUCCUGUGAAAAACUAUCAAGCGCAUCAGAGCAGAGUGACGAUGAUCCUGUUUGUCCUGGAGCUGGAGUGGGUGCUGAGCACAGGACAGGACAAGCAAUUUGCCUGGCACUGCUCUGAGAGUGGGCAGCGCCUGGGAGGUUAUCGGACCAGUGCUGUGGCCUCAGGCCUGCAAUUUGAUGUUGAAACCCGGCAUGUGUUUAUCGGUGACCACUCAGGCCAAGUAACAAUCCUCAAACUGGAGCAAGAAAACUGCACCCUGGUCACAACAUUCAGAGGACACACAGGUGGGGUGACCGCUCUCUGUUGGGACCCAGUCCAGCGGGUGUUGUUCUCAGGCAGUUCAGAUCACUCUGUCAUCAUGUGGGACAUCGGUGGGAGAAAAGGAACAGCCAUCGAGCUCCAAGGACACAACGACAGAGUCCAGGCCCUCUCCUAUGCACAGCACACGCGACAAUUGAUCUCCUGUGGCGGUGAUGGUGGGAUUGUCGUCUGGAACAUGGACGUGGAGAGGCAGGAGACCCCUGAAUGGUUGGACAGUGAUUCCUGCCAAAAGUGUGAUCAGCCUUUCUUCUGGAACUUCAAGCAAAUGUGGGACAGUAAGAAAAUUGGUCUAAGACAGCACCACUGCCGCAAGUGUGGGAAGGCCGUCUGUGGCAAGUGCAGCUCCAAGCGCUCCUCCAUCCCCCUGAUGGGCUUCGAGUUUGAAGUGAGGGUCUGUGACAGCUGCCACGAGGCCAUCACAGAUGAAGAACGUGCACCCACAGCCACCUUCCAUGACAGUAAACAUAACAUUGUGCAUGUGCAUUUCGAUGCAACCAGAGGAUGGUUACUGACUUCUGGAACUGACAAGGUUAUUAAGUUGUGGGAUAUGACCCCAGUCGUGUCUUGAUGACUCUCCCAGGAAUCAGAAAGAUAGUAUUUACUAAAGAAACGGUUGUUUUAACCCAAAUCAUUACCAGAGUGGUAAAGCAGACAUGUGAGAAGUAAGAAAGAAACUAAAGACCCUGAAUGAAUUUGCAGAUUACCCAUGUGCACAGUGGGGACCUGGCCAGUGAGCACUCGCAAGGGGACUCUUCCAACUUGUUCAUACAAUAUAAAAGAAGCUAUUUUUUUAACAAAUGGUUUAUACAGUCUGGCUGUGCUGCAUUGUUUUGAGUGUACCGAAAAAUCUGUGUGGGGUGUUUAAUUUUUAUACUUUUCAACACCCCAUUUUACUUGUUGCUUUGUCAGAGAAAUAAGGGAGGUAUCUACUCAGAGUAUUUUGGUCAUUAUACUUUCUGUGUUUACUUCAACAUGUGUCACGUGGCCAGCGGCUUUUUCUUCUCUUCCCUCUGCACCUACCUGCACCUUCUCUGCCUUUCCUGGAGGGGAUGUAUUUAUGUUAUUUAUUCCCAGUGUUUCUGCUUUCAUGUCCUCCUCAGUGGAGAGAUUUGGAAACUCAUCAUGUGGAUUCACCAGCCAGCUGCUGGAAUUGCCUGAAGAGCGAUUUGUUUGUAAUGUCUGCCUCAUUCACGUUCUUAUGAAGUAGAAAAGACUGUGUUUCUGCCUCAGUUGCCUCUGUCUUUCCCACAUUAAAAAAAAAAAUGCUGUGAGAAAGCUGCUCCCAACCAUGGUUAUCACAGAAGUAGAUUAUUUUAACUCAGAGCUUCAACGAUCAGUGCCUGGAUCAUUUAGAAUUCAGUUGGAGCCUCCUGAGCCUCUUGUUUUAGCUUUUUUGACGCAGCUCUCCCUCACUCGUAACAAUGAAAACAAAUGACACACACACAAAAUCCUACAUCAGCGGCCCUCAACCUUGUUGGCAGCAGGGACCGGUUUCAAAAUGAAACUGUUCCACCUCGGAUCAGCAGGCAUUAGCUUCUCAUAAGGAGCACGCAACCUAAAUCCCUCGCAUGCGCAGUUCACAAUAGAGUUUCUGCUCCUGUGAGAAUCUGACGCCACCGCUGAUCUGAUGGGAGGCGGAGCCCAGGCAGUAACACUUGCUUGCCCACUGCUCACGUCUGAUGGGUGCCCCCAUUCCUCACAGGCUAUGGACCAGUACCCAUCUGCAGCCCAGGGUUGGGGACCCCCACCAUACAUGCUCUGAAAAUAAGUGUCUUUAAGUUGUGUUUUUCUGUGUGACAUCAUCUCUGAACUUGAACAUGUUCAUUACGGCAAGAUUGUAAUCCUGCUGUAUUCCUCGCCCUCUGUAUUCUAUCCCUUUAAAAACUAGAUAUUUAAACAUUUUAUCCUAAUGUGUUUCAUCAGAACACUUUGCACACUUUCUUACUAAAACGGUAUGUGGGUGGUCCGAGACAGAAUGGUACCUACAGUGCAGGCUAUGUUUCUGUGGGAAUGGAAAAGAGGACUUUAGAAAGUGAACCUGAAGAACUCUUAUUUCUAAGGGAAUCCAGUCAAGCUUGAGAAAAUGAAAUAUUCUUGUGUGUAGUGAUUCAGCUCAGGAUAUUGAAGUCCCUUUUAAAAAUCUUAUUUUCACCUGUAAAAAUAGAAUAAAAAUUAAUGGCAAGCCUGCGCCAGGUGCCUGCCCCUCCUAAGCACUUUACACGCACAGCUCAUUCAACCUCACGUGUCGGGAGCAUCAGGGAGCUCACCAGUCUCUUGAGGAUCACAGGCCAAUUGCUUGUCCUUCCCGACCCAAGCCCCACCCCACAGUGUCUUGCUCUCUUCUGAUUUUACAGGUUUUUUGGCAGUAAUACACAUGGGAGUGAAAUUGAAAUCCUCCCUAUUAUUUUCCCUCUUUUCCUGGAAAGCCGUUUUUUGCCCUCACAAUCAUUCAUUACUUCUCUAACUAGGGGGAAGUACUACAAGCUGUCCUCAGGUACUGCCCCUACGUGUGUUUCCCUGGGAUGGGGCCUUGCUAGAGGUGAUUCUGCUGCCCCAGCAUUGGGAAGCAGGACCAGUGCAUGUGCCCCAUGCAGCCACGGUACAUGGAAGCUGUCACUUGAGCCAUCAGACCGGCUCAGCCCAUGUGACCGGAGCUCUGAAGAGGCACACACGCAUGCCCCGCACAGGCUGUUAGCACUUGUCGCCUCGCUGCCCUGGUCCAGACUACCCUUGCUUGCGUCAGUCAAAACUGUUGUAACUACUUUGAGUCUUUUCUGCAUGAUUGCUCUUUGAGAGAACUUUAACAAGGGAAUUAAAUUUAAAAUAUUCAAAUAUCUAUUUUGUAGUUUAUUACUAGAAGCUGCAGCCACUUACUAAGUUGUAUGUAAUAUAGGACUGUGUGUUGGAAAUGAGUAAUAGAGCUGAAUCACUCCAUUUUCCCUUCCUAAACUUUGAGCUUGGCCUGCCGGCAGAGAGAGGAACACAGUAUUAGGGCAGCAAAGGCCCAGGCGCCCAGCAAGCCUGUAUGGGUUCUGAGAUGGGUCUAGAUGCGUUCAGACCUCAUUCGGGAAGCAGAGUGUCCCCGUCAGAUCACAUAUGUCCUCUACAGUCGCUCUGGCCUGUGACCUUGCACGCCACUCUACCUUCUCCCUCCCAGCCCACAGAGCCACUCAGAGGCUGAAGCCACUUCACAGCCCACUGGUGUUGAGAAUCAUCAUCAGAAAACCAGAUAUGUCAAGGUAUCCAUUGCUCUUUCCUUUUCUCUCAUCUGUGUGGGUGCUUGAAUUUGGUGAAAUGCGUUUAGCAAACCAACUGUGUGUUUGUAAUACUGUGAAUUCUUGCGUUUUGCAUUAAGUGUCUCCCCCAUUUUUGUAAUUUGUAGAGAAAUAUGUGCUGGUGUUGGGUGUCUUCCAAGCAUUUUAUGGAAAUGGAGGCUCCAUUCCUUAGGAGUAAAAGCUGGCGCCAGCACUUGGCUCUUGUUCUGUCUAGGUGAACUCUCAUAAUUCUUGUUUUACCCUGUUGGAUUUGCACUUUACAUAUAUUUUUGCUCUAUUACUUAAACAUAUAGCAGCUUUUACAAAUAAUGCCUAACAUGCCUGCGCUGAGAAAGUGGCAGAUCUACACAUAUCAUACGCAGAGUUGUUCUCUACCUGAUGGGGCAAAACCAACCACAUGUUCUUGGUUCCUCCAAACGAAUGACAUUACUUGACAUUACUGCCUGAGUGUAUCUUCACAAUAGCAAAAUGGUUUGAGAUUAAGCAUUUGGAAUCUUAUGUCAUUUUGUAUGGGGUCAAUCCACCAUAACGUGUUUCUCAUUUGGUUUUAAUUAUUUCCAGAAAUCAUAAAGUCACAAAACUGGAAGGGAUCUUCAGAGAUCUAGAGUGUUUCAAGCAGAAAACACAUUAGUUAUACAGGGCAGUUAGAUAUGGCUGAGAUGUAAACAAGAGAAUCUAAAAGAAUGUUCAAGGAAUAGCUGUUUUUGAACAUUACUUAGUAAUGGCAUGAGUGGGAGGAGAGACUUUCAGCACCUUGAGACAGGGCGCUCUCUGGAACCAGCUUUGUUCCUCUUAUCGAAAGCAUAUAUGACAGUUUUUUUGGCUCCGGCCCUGUGGUGGGGGAGGUAAUUAUUGCCUUCAUCCACAUAAAUUCCUUCCUAUACAUUCCCCUCAGACCACCCCAGAGGCAAAACUGAAAUGGAAAUCCAGUGGCACUUAAAAUUCACCCUGCCCCGUUUGGCUGCGAUUCCCAGGCUUACAGCACUGCCCUUAUGGAAUAUCACAUUUUCAUUUUCUGAGAUUCAUUUUAUAAAAGUAAAGGCCAGGUGCCAUGGCUCACACCUAUAAUCUGAACACUUUGGGAGGACAAGGUGGGAGGAUUGCUGAGCCCAGGAGUUCAAGACCAGCCUGGGCCACACAGCAAGAUCCUGUCACUACCAAAAAUUCAAAACUUAGUUGGGUGUGGUGGCACACACCUGUAUUCCCAGCUACUCAGGAAGCUGAGGCGGGAGGAUCACUCGAGCCCAGGAAUUCAAGGAUGCAGUGAGCUAUGAUUGCACUACUGCAGUCCAGCCUGGGCAGCAGAGCAAGGCCCUGAAUAAAUAAACAAAAGUAUAAUUUAUUUUUGCCUGAUAUUAAUCACUUCUUAAGGCCCAAAUUUUUGUUUUUAAGCAAAAGGAUAGCUCUAAGUGUGGGUUGCAGUUACUGGACAUAAAUAUUCACUAAAUGAGAUUCCUUUGGUUAUGGCUGUUCAUAGAAUUUUAAUUCUAUGUCAGUGUUCUUGUUCACUAAGAUAUUUCGAAGUGAGAGAAAGCAUUUUACCAAUACAUUCUUAUUUUUUCUCCUUUAAAAUAAUAUUGAAUUUUUCCUGGUACGAAGACAGAUAUUUAUUAACUUGAUUGGAAAACACAGAAAUUAAGAUCAUGUUGAACACUGAGUUAUCUAGAUGAUCCCUGAGAUUUGAAUGUUCAUGUCAACCGUGUUGAGCGCUCACCAGCCACCAGGCUUUAGGCACUGGCAGUGCAAGGUGUCUGAGGCCCAUUCUCAGGCUGGGCAGAGGUCACACAGUGAGUAAAUGGGUCUUUUCAGUGCAAUGUGGUUAUGAUAGAGGCAUGCCAGGGUGCCACUAACCCAGCAGGUGUGGCAGGAGGGGCUUCACAGAGGAAAGGGACUUUGAGCUCAGUGUUAAAGGAUGAGGAGUGAGUCAUAAGGGGGAAAAAUGGAAAUGACUUUCCAGGCUUCAGAAACAGCAUAAACAAACAAAGGCCUGAGAGCUGGAGUCAGUGUGGUGUGUCCAGGGAUCACAAGUGGGCUGGAGCUGCCGGAGAACAGCCAAGUGGCUCAGCUGCCAUCCCAGAAUUGAGCUCGUCACUAUCAGAUGCUGCUGCUCCCUGGCCUCAGAGGAAAGCAGCACACAGCUCACCACGAGGGGUUUCCCCAGAGGCUCCUCCUGCAGCCAAUGCUACUAUUAGUUUAUAUUAUAAUAGUAUCAGUUUCUUUUUCUUUGGAAAUCCCUAGAACUGUUAACUGAAGGUGACUCAGGGUAACUAAUUCUGGAUCUUUGGGUGCACAGCCUCUCACUGGAGUCUGAGAGGAGGAGGUGGAGACUAUCAGUGCACGGCCCGCAACCAGGAAGGACUCCCAGACUAACGCCAAAGGUGUGUUGGGCUCAGCUGCUCCACUGUGGAAAAGGAAAGCCCUGGCCCUGUGGCAGGAGAGGAUUGUUCUAGUCAAGUGUGGCGUUGCACGGACAGGCGGUGCCGAGUGUUUGGGUGCAGACACAGGCAGCUGCUGCCCUCCACUUCCUGCUCUUGCAAGUCACAGAUGAUUCCAGUACAAUGUGGGAGGUCCUCCUUACAGGGGCACUUGCAACAGGAAGGCAGAGAGUUUCGUCAAUUCAGGUACAGGUCUGUCUGGGAGACCUGGCCCUGUGGAGGCAGGAACACCGUGCAGGGGCAUGGCAGCGCCUGUCUUUGCUAUCACAUCAUUUGCCUUUUCCUUGUAGGACCCAAAGAUCUAUGUCCAAAACUUAGUCCAGAAACAUCUGCAUUCCUGUUUAAACUUCAGCUCAGUUUCUUAACCAAGAACCACGUCAACCCUCCAGGGUUGUGGUUUGUAUUUUUGCCUUUAAGCAUUAUCUCCUUUCCACCAAGAAGCCUACUUAGGUUUAACACAUGAAAGCAGUGUCUAAAAAUUAGAUCGGUCCUAAAUUGGAAUGGGAUGUCUUCCUUGCAUGUCCCAUACCAGGGAAUUUUUUUAACACACAGUGUAGAGCCUUUGCCAGAGAUGUUGAAAGGGAGAUUAAAGGCUUGAGGGAUGAAUUUGAUCAUCAUUCUUAAAGUCCCUUCCAAUCCUGUGAUUCUCUGAUUCCCUGAGUCUCGUUUAUUAUUGGACAUGCCUAGCCCAUCACCAGUGACCUGCCCGCAUAUUGCUGGCUUCCCUUGGAUAACGGAGAGCCUAUCACCACAUGCCUUUGUUGUCUUCCAUCAUAUCAAGUGAGUUGCUUUCUGGACUUUUUCCAUCUAGAGCCUGCUAGGUUUGGUUUUGAGAAAAGAUGGUGAAGUUUCUUUUCAUGAGUUUGUAGGGCAAAAAAAAUUCUUUUUAAAGAUGGUAAGGGUGGAAAUUAAUCAUGGUACCAUCUCAUUAAAAAUAGAUACCUCAAAAUGUUUACCUUUACAAGUCAAGAAGAGUAUCUGACUUUCUUGGAAGUGUCAAGAAUUGCAGGUUGGCUGAAAAGUUAGAUUGAGAAUCUGACCUUGUUACUUAUGAUUCUUUUUUCCCUUGGUUCUCGGGGAUGCAUGAGAAGGUGAGCUGUCACUCACAAAAAAAGGGAAAAUGAUUUGAAAAAUGUUUCACAUAUACACUUUUUAUCAUUUUAGUGGAUGGCAGCCUUACGUCAGUAGUAUAUGCCACUAUGAAGUAUGGCCAAAACCCUAGCGUCACUUGUAACCAUUGUACUCUUAUGGAUUUGUGUCUUACACCAUUUGCCUUGCUUUUUAAAUGACUUUGUUUUUCAAGGUGCUGUCAUUUUGCAAAAGGAAAUCUUUAUAUGAAAUGUACAAAAACCGUUACUAACUGGACAACAGGGAAGGUGCUGGCCCCACAUUAGUGCCUGCCCACCGCUCUACUUCUAACCAGGGACACGGAUCUUCCAUUCUCUACAUCCACCGGACUGCAGCCCAAGUCUGGACCUGGCUGCAGUGGGCAUAUUACCGUAUGGAUAUCUUUUUCUUUCUUUUUUUAAAGUGAGGAGAUUCUUCAGGGGGUCAGGCUGAGAAUGUAAUAAGCCUGACAUUGGAACAGAUUUCUCCCGUGUGGUCUAGCUGGACCCCUCCGGCAUUUGCCACACUCCCUGCCAGUCCUGACAUUGACUUCCUGAAUGUGAUUAGGUGGUAAUGAGCAAGAAUUUCCUAGGAUAUUGAAACAUCUGUAUCCAGGCCCCCAAUCAAAUGCUGCUGAAUAUUGUGAAUGUUUUUACUCCGCUCACUUUCCCACUGUGCUUUCCUCUAACCAAAAUAUACGUGUAGCCAUUACCAAUGUACAACUCUCAAUGCGGAGUUGCCGCCACGGUUUAAAAUAAAUCUCUGUGAAAACCUUUCUGCAGCUAUGGUCCCAUCACGGUUACAUGUGGCCACGCACACACCGACAACCUUGCUGUGCUGUUUAGCCCUGUGGGUUCUGUCCAGUUGGUGGGAGGGGGAGGUUCCAGACCACUCCACCUGCUGUCUAGAUGCCAGGGAGAGCUGCUGUUUGGAGGUGAAGAUGAGCCCUGUUCACCACAGUCUAAGCACAGCACACGGGCUCAAGCCAUGGAGCCCUUUUCCUUCAUCAUGUAAGUCAGCUUUUUCUUGUGCUUAGUAAACUUUUCCAGUGAGGAGAAAUGACUUCGGGGCAAACACUGCCAGGGAAAGCCUCAUUUAAAACUUGUGAGGUUCAUUUUAUGGAGAAGAAAAAUAGGUGCAAAGGCACCAAGUGACCUGCAUGCUAUGGAAUCACCGUUGAGGGGGUGGCUGGGUUGCCCCGUCCUGGUGCUGCCAGCACAGCGUCGCCCACACCCAGCAUUGCUGAGGCCCAUCAUCCUCCUGCAGAAAAGGAGGCAUGCAGUUAAAUGGAGCUGGUGCUUGCUUGAUAGCGCCUCCUUUUGUCAGAAAGACGCUGAUGUUUCAGGCUGGCACACCCAGAAAAAUCCCUUCCUUGUGGUCCUUGGCUGAUGAUGAGCCCUGGAUCAGAGUGUCUCCAGGACCACUGAGAAGCUGCAGCCGUCUGGGUUUUCCUCUGCUAUGGGGGAUGAGUUACGUUUAUUCCACCAUGGACACCAAGAAUGUAUGUAGAUGUAUUCUAAAUCUGCUCAUUGGUUUUAUUACAACUUUUCCUGGAGUCACUAAGAGGUAAAAUGGUGUAAAUUAGAGGUUUUAUCAAAGUGUAGUACCAGAAUGCCAGAUGCAUUACUGAAGCCACUCCUAAUCUUAAGCAAAUGUAAACUAGGCCUCAUUAAAUUGUUUGUGUAAAUAUG